AGUCCUGCAGCCCCAGCCCAGCCGUCCCCCGCGGGCGUGGCAGGUCCUGAGUCAGGGCCUGUCCGUGGCCAGCAUCCCUGCUGGGCGAUUGAGCAGCGGGAAGCUGCUUGGACCCAGUCUCAAACUUAACCCUCAUCUAGCACCCGGGCAGGCCUCCUGGGUUGCAGGGACUUGAGAAAAGGCAGAGUUCUCAGGUCCUAGGAAGCUGGGGCACGCUGGCGUGACAAGCGUCCCGGAGAAAGCCAAGCCCUCGGGGAGCUGGGGACCGCAGCAGGGCUGCAGUCACAUCCUGCGCGGGUGGGCGGCGGGCCAGGCCUUCAGUUGUUUCGGGACGCGCCGAGCUUCGCCGCUCUUCCAGCGGCUCCGCUGCCAGAGCUAGCCCGAGCCCGGUUCUGGGGCGAAAAUGCCUGCCCUUCACAUCGAAGAUUUGCCAGAGAAGGAAAAACUGAAAAUGGAAGUUGAGCAGCUUCGCAAAGAAGUGAAGUUGCAGAGACAACAAGUGUCUAAAUGUUCUGAAGAAAUAAAGAACUAUAUUGAAGAACGUUCUGGAGAGGAUCCUCUAGUAAAGGGAAUUCCAGAAGACAAGAACCCCUUUAAAGAAAAAGGCAGCUGUGUUAUUUCAUAAAUAACUUGGGAGAAACUGCAUCCUAAGUGGAAGAACUAGUUUGUUUUAGUUUUCCCAGAUAAAACCAACAUGCUUUUUAAGGAAGGAAGAAUGAAAUUAAAAGGAGACUUUCUUAAGCACCAUAUAGAUAGGGUUAUGUAUAAAAGCAUAUGUGCUACUCAUCUUUGCUCACUAUGCAGUCUUUUUUAAGAGAGCAGAGAGUAUCAGAUGUACAAUUAUGGAAAUAAGAACAUUACUUGAGCAUGACACUUCUUUCAGUAUAUUGCUUGAUGCUUCAAAUAAAGUUUUGUCUUGGGAAGAUGAGUGUUGGUGAUUUAAGAAGACACUUUUCAUGCAUUAACUUUUAUAUUUCUCCCCGUAAUCUUUUGGGUGUGGAGUAUGAUUGGGUUUGGAAUAUGAUUCAGAAGGUUAGGUGGUUCGACAGAUCACAUCUCCAAACCCUGCGUCAAUGGUUUAGAGUGCUGAGUUCUGACCUCUGGAACGUGUUUGAUCUAACCUUAACUAUUAAGAAACUGAGCAGGUAGAAUUCCUAUAACAUUGACAGAAGUCAGAUUAUCUGAGUCAGGAACAAGGCCAAGCCACAUCUAUGUUAGUACUUCCCUAGUUUAUCAUCAUUUAGAUCUUCUUAAUAGUGUUCCUGUAGUAGUAGCCUUGAAGAAAAUACUGAGUUGGGGUUCAGGAAGAGUGCCCUGCCUCUCUGCCGUGUAGUGGCCAGGCCAGCCCUGGCUUUGAGAGCCAGUACUUAUUCCUGCACAGAGCUACAUCUCCCAUGUGCUCUCCAGGUCUUGGGCAUGGCACUACUCCAGUUCUGUGGCAUUGGUGCAGACACUUGGACCUCUGCACUCAUGCUUGCCAGCAUUUUCCAGCAGGCCUGGGCCAAACAUGCCUUUUUUUCUUCUCCUCCAAAGGAACCAGUGAAUCUUUGCCCACUUUAAAGAUUAGUUGGUCUUUUUCUUACUGAUUUGUAGGAAUUCUUCAUAUAUUCUGGCCAUUUAUUCGUGUUUGGUGAUAUGUGUUGCGAAUACCUUCUCCCAGUCUGUGGCUUACCUUUUCACAGUGACCUUCCCUUCAGUGGUUUUAUCCUGCAGGGCAACACGUCAGAGUAUAACUCCUGCUCAAGUUCAUAACAAAGGUACCUGAAGCCCAAACCUCACAAAAAGGGACCUUUCUUUCUCACCUUGAGCAUUCUCCCGCUUCUUCUCCGUCUUUUGGGUCAAAAUUGCUCCAAGUUUGAGCCAAAAGAAAAACGUGGAAAAACCCUUGCUGGUUAGCUCUAGCUCAAAUGGACUUAGUCAUUAACUUGACCUGCAAUUUUCAAUGUGGCACCAGAAGCCAAUGUUUCUCCUUGACUAGCUCUUUUCUCCCACUUACACAUGUAGGUAUACCUUACUAUCAAGCGAGAGAGGCGCCUGUAACCUGUAGCAGCUUUCUAAAGUAUAUCAGCAUCCUCGUUCUGAAAUUCCUUUCCUUUCCCUCUCUGGGAAAGAACAGAAUACCCCAGGCUUUUGAAAAAUAGUUUACACAGACCAAAAGCAGAAACUAUUUCCUUCAGUUUCCUGACACUGUCCAAGUGAUGACAUCAAUUGGCAUUACUGAGAGCCCAGGGAUAAUUUUAGCCCAAAACUACUACUCCUAGGAAGGAGUAGUAUGAUCUACUACUCUUAGGAAGGAUUUAGGAAUAGUAAAGGUGUAUUUCUUCCAAACAGCAUAGAACUAUUAGUACUAUUAGUCAUUUAACAUUUAACAUGGCAUGGGAUUUUAGAGCUUUGGUGCCUGUAAAGUUUUACUUCUAUUAGCUGUUUCAUUUCUUUGCACUUAUAAAGUUUUCUUCUGUUGCCUAUGAAAGCAAACAUUUAUUCCGGUUACUGGCAAGGCAGUUUAAAUCACCUGCUUCUUUCAUGAAAGGCCAAGACAAUACAUUUAUUCCCUAACUUGUUGGGAGUUGCGAUUACAAGUCUAUAUCCUGAUUUCUAUUAGCACAUUCAGCUAUCCAUUUGUGUACACUCCCAAGUCCUAGCUUUUGCUCUUCAUGUCUCUUUCAACCAUAUGAUCAAUCAGUUGGACGACUUCUGGUUUUUCCUGAAUAAAUAUCUAAUCUUAUAGGUGCUUCUAUUAAAUAUAAUUCUGUUUCUUUUUCUUACCAUUUAUCAUUAUAACCCAGCCAACAUGUAGAAGUGCAAUAAAAAUAUUUUAAUUUUCAACUGUUCAACUGCUAAAAUUAUUAGCUUGUAAUUAAAAAAGAAAAAAUACAUCCACUAUAUAUUUAGAUAUAUUGUAAAUGUAACCUUUGGUGACUGAUAAUUUGUUAAGUAGAAUUUAAAUUAUGUAUCCAAUUUAUUCAAAGUGUAUAGUUGUGUAAUUAUUUACUAUUUGAUUAAAAAUAGUUAUCAUGCA